AGAUUCUGUUGUCAGCUUCUUAUGUAGCAGCUGUGUAAAAAUGUUAAUAAACAUUGAAAAUUAGUAUAAAGUGUUGUGUUCUAGUUUAACAUUCAUAUUUAUAUAUGGGCAGUACAAUAAAAUUAUAAAUAAUAGGCUUUAAGGUGUGAAAGAUCAGAUACUUUUCAUUCCUGCUUUUUCUUGUCACCUCAUUGAAACUCAUUUUUCAUAUUUUUUCCAAUCCAACUGAUUCUAUUUUUAUAGAGUUGUAGACAAGAAUAAAUUAUCUGUUCAUAUCUCCAAUGCAUCUCUUGGGAAUUCUUCCUUAACUUUGCCCAGCUUAUAAAUAUUGAGGAUAUUAUUGCAGCUUGUUUUGGAGAUCCAGAUGGUUCAAGUGUUUGGCUCAUCAUGAUAAAAAGUCUUUUGGAAAAUUUAAGUAUGGUUUCAAUUUAUAUAAUAAUAAUGUUUGUAAUAGUUAAGUGAUUAUGUAUUCAAUGUGUUAUGUCUUUUGUUUAUUAUUAAAUAUACAACAGAAAAAUAGCCACUGCAUAUUUUGCUAUUAUCUCUAACUUUAUUAAUAGCAUUUUGGUUUGCUUAAAAUGAAGGAUUUGCAUUGCUUGUGACAGUCUUGGGGAAGCUCUAAUCCCUAGGUGUAAUUUCCAACAUUCCUCUAGAGCCAUCACAAAUAAAUGUACAAUCUAAGUAAAAUAGUGUGCUUGCCAAACAAAUCUAGUUUCGAAUUAAAUUCAUACCCAUCCCAGAUUGCAUCCCCUUUGUCUCUCCUAUAUGGAAAUUCUGACAUUCAGUGAGCAUGACUCACUGUUGUUGUAGAUGUUGAUUGCUAGUACCUGAAAACUAAAAGAAUUAUAAUAGAGCAAAACAUUAAUAUAAGUUUGAAUUAAUUUUUAAAAAAUUAUCUCAUAUUACAAGUCUUUGCUGGUUAUAGGCUAAGGGCUAGAUAUUUUCCUCCCAGAAAUGCUGUUUAAGUCUCUAUGGUUUUUUUUUUUCUUUAAAAUGUGCAGAUUGAAGUUACAUGUUUUUUUGUUUGUUUGUUUGUUUGUUUGUUUUUUAUUUUAAAGAUGGAGUCUCACUCUGUCGCCCAGGCUGGAGUGCAGUGGCGUGAUCUUGGCUCACUGCAACCUCUGCCUCCUGGGUUCAAGCGAUUCUCCUGCCUCAUUCUCCAGAAUAGCUGGGAUUACAGGUGCACGCCACCAUGCGCGGCUAAUUUUUGUAUUUUUAGUAGAGAUGGGGUUUUGCCAUGUCAGCCAGGCUGGUCUCUAACUCCACCGCGCCCAGCUUGAAGUUAACACAUUUUUUAUUUGGUUAGGAUAUAAAUUGAGUAGUACCAGUGAUACUUUCAUUUUGUCCAUUUUGAGAGUGAUUAACUGUCAUUAGUAGAAACUUGACGAUGUCAUUUACACUUAUUAGGUUAAAUAAAUAGAGAAUUAGUUUUAGUGUGUUGAAUGUAUUUAGAGAUUUCCAACAAGCCAUUCUGGGUCCUGAAAAAGCAAAUCCAUUUGAACCAAAGCAUCCAUUUAGUUCAUUUUGUAGUGAUAAAUCUGUUAUAUAGUAACAGCUUAUUGGGUGAAAAUAAUUCAGGCAGUUUACAGAGUGUUUAUGCCAGGUACUUUGCUUUGAAAUUGUCAGUAUGGUGAUAAACCACAUACAGUGUAAUCAGUAUAAUCCUUGGUUUCAUAAAGAACAUAAUCUAUCAAGAAGGACUUAUAUUAAAGUAGGCACCCAUAAAAUUAGGCUGUAGGCCGGGCGCGGUGGCUCACGCUUGUAAUCCCAGCACAUUGGGAGGCCGAGGCGGGCGGAUCACGAGGUCAGGAGAUCGAGACCAUCCUGGCUAACACGGUGAAACCCCGUCUCUACUAAAAAUACAAAAAAAUUAGCCGGGCCUGGUGGCGGGCGCCUGUAGUCCCAGCUACUCGGGAGGCUGAGGCAGGAGAAUGGCGUGAACCUGGGAGGCAGAGCUUGCAGUGAGCCGAGAUUGCGCCACUGCACUCCCACCUGGGCCACAGAGCGAGACUCCGUCUCAAAAAAAAAAAAAAAAAAAAAAGAAAUUAGGCUGUAGAGAGAAGGAAGUUGUGCAUACAGUGGAAGCAUUCGGAUCUAACUCUCCUUCCGGGAUCAAGACUAAGGAGGACCUGAACGAGGAGCAGGAAGACUUGAGUGAACUGAAUUCAAAGCUGCAAGAUACUUUGGAACAGAUUGAGGAACAGCUGGACGUAGCUCUUUCCAAAAUCUGCAAGAAUUUUGACAUUAACCAUUAUACCAAGGUUCAACAAGCUUAUCGACUUCUUGGAAAAACACAGACAGCAAUGGAUCAACUUCAUAUGCACUUCACCCAAGCCAUUCACAACACCGUGUUUCAAGUUGUUCUUGGUUAUGUGGAACUAUGUGCAGGAAACACAGACACAAAAUUCCAAAAGCUGCAAUAUAAGGAUCUCUGUACACAUGUUACACCAGACAGCUAUAUUCCAUGCCUUGCAGACCUGUGCAAAGCACUAUGGGAAGUUAUGCUCAGCUAUUAUAGGACUAUGGAAUGGCAUGAAAAGCAUGACAAUGAGGAUACUGCUUCAGCUUCUGAAGGGAGUAAUAUGAUAGGUACUGAAGAAACUAAUUUUGAUCGUGGCUACAUAAAAAAGAAAUUAGAACAUGGACUUACACGAAUAUGGCAGGAUGUUCAGCUAAAAGUAAAAACCUACUUGCUUGGAACUGAUUUGUCUAUAUUCAAAUAUGAUGAUUUCAUCUUUGUUUUGGAUAUAAUCAGCAGGUUGAUGCAAGUUGGAGAAGAAUUUUGUGGUAGCAAGUCUGAAGUUUUACAGGAAUCUAUUAGAAAACAAAGUGUCAAUUAUUUCAAGAAUUACCAUAGAACACGGCUCGAUGAACUGAGAAUGUUCUUAGAGAAUGAGACUUGGGAACUUUGUCCUGUUAAGUCAAAUUUCAGCAUCUUGCAACUUCAUGAAUUUAAAUUCAUGGAACAGUCUCGCUCCCCAUCAGUUUCACCUAGUAAACAGCCAGUCUCAACUUCUUCAAAAACAGUGACCUUGUUUGAGCAGUACUGUAGUGGUGGGAAUCCAUUUGAAAUUCAGGCCAACCACAAAGAUGAAGAAACAGAAGAUGUCUUAGCUUCUAAUGGGUAUGAAUCUGAUGAACAAGAAAAGAGUGCCUAUCAAGAGUAUGACAGUGACAGUGAUGUUCCUGAGGAACUCAAACGAGACUAUGUGGAUGAGCAGACAGGAGAUGGUCCUGUGAAAAGUGUUUCUCGGGAAACUCUAAAAAGCAGGAAGAAAUCAGAUUACAGUCUAAAUAAAGUGAAUGCACCUAUCUUAACAAAUACAACAUUGAACGUCAUAAGACUUGUUGGAAAAUAUAUGCAGAUGAUGAACAUUCUUAAGCCAAUUGCCUUUGAUGUUAUUCAUUUCAUGUCUCAACUAUUUGAUUAUUACUUGUAUGCAAUAUAUACCUUUUUUGGUCGGAAUGAUUCAUUGGAAUCAACUGGACUCGGCCUUAGUAGUAGUAGACUAAGAACAACUCUAAACAGAAUACAAGAAAGCCUUAUUGAUCUAGAAGUUUCAGCUGAUCCUACUGCCACACUCACAGCAGCAGAAGAAAGAAAGGAGAAGGUGCCAAGUCCACACCUCAGUCACCUAGUGGUUUUGACAUCUGGGGAUACGCUGUAUGGGUUGGCAGAAAGAGUGGUAGCCACGGAAUCCUUGGUAUUCUUGGCUGAACAGUUUGAGUUCCUUCAGCCACAUCUGGAUGCUGUGAUGCCUGCAGUCAAAAAGCCCUUUCUUCAGCAGUUCUAUUCUCAGACAGUCUCAACCGCCAGUGAACUACGGAAACCAAUUUACUGGAUUGUAGCUGGUAAAGCCCUUGAUUAUGAACAGAUGCUGCUUCUCAUGGCUAAUGUGAAAUGGGAUGUAAAAGAAAUUAUGUCACAGCACAACAUAUAUGUAGAUGCACUAUUAAAGGAAUUUGAGCAGUUUAACAGGAGGCUAAAUGAAGUUUCUAAGAGAGUUCGCAUACCCUUGCCUGUGUCUAAUAUACUUUGGGAACAUUGUAUACGAUUGGCUAAUCGAACUAUUGUAGAAGGAUAUGCCAAUGUCAAGAAAUGCAGUAAUGAGGGUCGUGCCCUGAUGCAAUUGGAUUUUCAACAGUUUUUAAUGAAACUUGAAAAACUAACAGAUAUUAGACCCAUUCCUGAUAAAGAAUUUGUAGAAACUUAUAUUAAAGCUUAUUACCUAACUGAGAAUGACAUGGAACGGUGGAUCAAAGAGCACAGGGAAUAUUCAACGAAGCAGCUGACCAAUCUGGUGAAUGUUUGCCUGGGAUCCCAUAUCAAUAAGAAAGCAAGACAAAAACUUCUAGCAGCUAUAGAUGAUAUAGACAGACCUAAAAGAUAAUGAACACAGCUCUCUUUCCUCAAUGGCAUUGAUCCUCACUCAACAUAUAUGACCUGAAAGCCAGUUUUUUUAUGCACUUCUGACAACUAUCUGCUAAGAAAACUUUGUGCAUGUUUUUUUGACUGGAAAGUGGAAAAUAUUGAAAUGUGUGUGGUGUUCUCAUGACUUUUAUAUGCUGUGGUCUCUUCAACUUUUGGUCUCAUUUGUUGUAAUCUGAAAUGAUGUUGCCGCCUUGUCAUAACAAUGGUUAUGUGACUACAGUUAUACAUUUUACAGAAGAAUGUACCAUAAGUAUAUAAUUAGAAGAACAGUGGCUUAAUAUAUGUAUGGGAAGUUUAUGGAAAAUGAAGUUGGCACUUUUCUACCCUCUGAGCUUGGUUCUUAAUAAGCAUAAUGUGAGGGUGAAUAUGUAGUAUCUCCUAAUUAUGAGCACUGCAUGAGAAUUAAAAAACACAUGUAAGUAAAAUAGUUGAAAAAUCAGUAUGUUCUCUGUUUUUAAAAUGUCAAAGUUUAUGUCAGGGUUAAUUUAGUUAUAACAAAGUGAUCAUAAUGGUGAAAUUUAAUAAAUAUACUCUAGUAUGAUCAGCCUAUGUGAGACUACAUUUUGAUUUUUUGUGUGGCAUGCAGAUGUCAUGAACUAUAGUGCAGCUUUUAGUGUGUUCUAAUUUUAAUUGUUUUAUAUCCUGAAACCAAUGGUGAAAAGUAAUUUCAUUGAGGGUACCUUUUCAAUGCCUGAGUAGCAUACAGAAUCAUGAUUAUGAGACUUUCUUUUAUCUUUCUUUAUAAAAAUAUGUGGUUUUUUUGUUGAAAGUUUUGGUCUCUUUAAAUUCAGAUUUUGUCUUAGGACAGUAAAACCCAGGUUGACUGACUCAGGAAACAGUUGUCUGCUAGUCACUCAUAAAUGUACGGUCAUAUGUUCACUCUUCUUAAAUAUCCACCUUUUAUAACACAAAUGUAAAAUAGUAUCAGUCUAGCCAAUGAUGAACUCUGGAAUCCACUUAGUCUUCAGUAAGUAUGUGCUGUUCCUCUAAACUUUGCCCUGAAGCCAGGGAUCUUCUCCUAAUGUAUGUGACAUAAAAAUCCAUUUUCCAUGUACUCUUGCCAACUGUCUGAUAAGGAAUUUUGUGUGUGUUCUUUCUGACUGGAGAGUGGAGGACAUCUAAGCUUGUGUGGCAUUGGUCCAAUGAUUGCCAUGCAUGACCUGUAACAUCAACAGCUCACAGAAUCCUAAGGAAUCAUGUGAGAAACAGGCCUUGGGUCUUAUGAGUCUUCUGGGACCUAAGGUGAUAAAAUGGAUGGCACAGAAUGGCAUGUGAUCAAGCAUGGAGGUGAUAAGGAAACAAUUGCUACUCUGUGUCCAUCAGUCCCUGCGAUGUCUGUAAAUGCACAGUGUAAUGUGAAGCACUUUCAGAAUAUGUUUGUGUGUGUCUGUAUGCUGAGUGUUUUCUUUUCAUCCUCUCAUGUCGGAGUUCAUUUACUGUCAAUUUAAAACUUUCCUCUUGUAAAAAGGUAUGAGUUUGGUGCCAUUAUGAUUUGGUUGUGGCUAGAUUAUAUACUUGUGAAGUAGAUUCUGCCUGUAGCCAUUAUUUAUAUGCAGCCACUUGAAGAAAACAAACAUGAGAUAAGCUUGGUCCUUGAGUUUAAAUGGCAUAUUUAGCUGGGCACAUAAAGAGCUAAUCAAUCUUUUAAAAUUUGCAGUUGAUGAAGAGCUGCUUAUUUUUCUCUUCUACAUGGAUUUUAUAGUUGGUUUCCUUUAAUUUCUACUUUAGUUGGCCCUAGAUAAUAUGAACAGGAAUCACCUGCCUGGUAGAGCCCAGUGUUUUCCAAGGUAAUAGGAAUUGAUACAAAAGAAUUACUUAUCUUGUUAGAGACUCGACCAUGCAAUCUGACAGACCUUUUAACCUACCCUUACUUUGCUUUCUCCAUCUUCAAAAUGAAAUGGUGGAUCUUUUUAAUGCUUUUUGAAAAAGGUUUUUUUUUUUUUUUUUUUUCAUUAAAAGGUAGCUUAAUAAGUGCUAGCUAGCAUCAAAACAGUAACAGGAGGUUUGAGUCAUGAAGUUACCUAAUCACAAGAGAGUUACCAGACAUUUCUCAAAUACUUUAUACAGUAAUAUUGAGUUAUAACCAUGUAACAUUUUAUGAAACUAAUUUUCAGAUAAAUACAAUUGAAAAGCUGAGAAUGUAAAUGGAAUUAUACGUGUUCCAAAAACUAUCAUUACCAAAAAUUUAUUAUUUUUGAGUCUAAACUUUCCUUAACUUUGACAUUUUCCAUGAAAGUUUCCUGUAGAAUUUACCAUGGGAGCAUGGUAAAUUAGCAUUCCCUGAGAAAGAAUGAUCAUUUCUACAAAUACAUUGUCUUGCAUUUAAAAAUGCUAGGGGGGCACAUAGCAAUUCAAAUGAACUAGUUUGCUUUGGUUUAUAAAACCAACAGAGAUUUUGUAAGUUCACUUUAACUAAUAAACUCAUUUACACAACUUAUUAAAUGAAUUUCUCUUGAAACCAGGGCCAUAUGGUAUUUUAUCAUAUCUUUAAAUAAAAUUUCGAAAUUUCUAUUUAGCUGAGUGCUAAAGUGAAACUUUGUUAGAUUAAAUAGCUUUUUCUUAACUCACCAAAAAGUAGUAAAAGGCUUGUAAUUCAAUUCACCUUGUAAGCAUAGUUGUCUUUUGUAAUAAAAAACUAGAUCUGAA